CUCAACAGCAGCACUUCCGGGUUGGGAGAAAGGUGGCGGCGCUUUCGGAGGGUAAGUUGAAAGCGCCUUUGUUGUUUCUGUUUUUCAAAAUGCGCGCGUAAAAACUCAGCGUGGGGUGGUGGGUUUCCCCGUCUUCUGGGAGACCCGCCUUUUGGCCUGAGGUCUCCAGGCCGCGGUCUUUGCCCCAGGCCUUAUCUCGGGGAAACUGAGGCUUGGGUGUUUUUUUUUUUUUUUUUUAAAGAUGGAGUUUUGCUCUUGUCGCCCAGGCUGGAGUGCGGUGGCGCGAUCUCGGCUCACUGCAACCUCCGCUUCCUGGGUUCAAGCGAUUCUCCUGCCUCAGCCUCCCGAGUAGCUGGGAUUAUAGGCGCCCGCCACCAAGCCUAGCUAAUUUUUGUAUUUUUAGUAGAGACAGGGUUUCACCAUGUUGGCCAGGCUGGUCUCGAACUCCUGACUUCAGGUGAUCCACCCGCCUCGGCCUCUCAAAGUGCUGGGAUGACAAGCGUGAGCCACCGCGCCCGGCCGCGGCUUGGGUCUUUGGGAGUGAGAAGAUGCAGAAUUCACAUCUGGUUAGUUCCUCCAGUCUCAGCCCUGGAGCGCCCACCCGGGAGCAGAGCGGGGUCUCUCUCGCACCCCAAAGGCGGAAUAAAAUGGAAGGAGAAUCAAGCAGAUUUGAAAUCCACACUCCAGUUUCUGACAAGAAAAAGAAAAAGUGUUCUAUACAUAAGGAAAGACCUCAGAAACAUUCCCACGAAAUUUUCAGAGACUCCUCCCUGGUGAAUGAACAGUCUCAAAUAACUAGGAGGAAAAAGAGGAAAAAAGAUUUCCAGCAUCUCAUUUCUUCUCCUUUGAAAAAAUCCAGAAUCUGUGAUGAGACUGCAAAUGCCACUUCCACACUCAAAAAGAGAAAAAAGAGAAGAUAUAGUGCUUUGGAGGUGGACGAGGAAGCAGGUGUUACAGUUGUCCUUGUGGAUAAAGAAAAUAUUAACAACACACCAAAGCAUUUUAGAAAGGAUGUUGAUGUUGUUUGUGUUGAUAUGAGCAUAGAACAGAAGUUACCAAGAAAGCCUAAAACAGACAAAUUUCAGGUACUUGCUAAGUCACAUGCACAUAAAUCAGAAGCCCUGCACAGUAAAGUUAGGGAGAAAAAGAAUAAAAAGCAUCAGAGGAAAGCUGCAUCCUGGGAGAGCCAGCGGGCAAGGGACACCCUGCCUCAGUCAGAAUCCCACCAGGAGGAGUCCUGGCUUUCUGUGGGUCCAGGGGGUGAAAUUACAGAACUACCAGCAUCUGCUCAUAAAAACAAGUCUAAGAAAAAAAAGAAAAAGUCCAGUAACCGGGAAUAUGAGACACUGGCCAUGCCUGAAGGAUCGCAAGCAGGCAGAGAGGCCGGGACUGAUAUGCAGGAAUCCCAGCCUACUGUGGGCUUGGAUGAUGAAACUCCACAACUACUAGGACCUACUCACAAAAAAAAGUCUAAGAAAAAAAAGAAGAAAAAGUCCAAUCACCAGGAAUUUGAGGCAUUGGCCAUGCCUGAAGGAUCACAAGUGGGCAGUGAGGUUGGGGCUGAUAUGCAGGAAUCCCGGCCUGCUGUGGGCCUGCAUGGUGAAACUGCAGGAAUACCAGCACCUGCUUAUAAAAACAAGUCUAAGAAAAAAAAGAAAAAGUCCAAUCACCAGGAAUUUGAGGCAGUGGCCAUGCCUGAGAGCCUCGAGAGUGCAUACCCUGAAGGAUCACAGGUGGGCAGUGAGGUUGGGACUGUGGAAGGCAGUACAGCUCUUAAAGGGUUCAAGGAAUCCAACAGUACAAAGAAGAAGUCUAAGAAAAGGAAGCUUACGUCUGUCAAAAGGGCACGAGUGUCUGGUGAUGAUUUUUCAGUGCCCAGUAAGAACUCUGAGAGCACACUCUUUGAUUCAGUAGAAGGUGAUGGCGCCAUGAUGGAAGAAGGUGUGAAAUCUAGGCCCCGACAAAAGAAAACCCAGGCCUGUUUGGCAAGCAAGCACGUGCAAGAGGCGCCAAGGUUAGAACCUGCAAAUGAAGAACACAAUGUGGAAACAGCUGAAGAUUCCGAAAUAAGAUACUUAUCUGCAGAUUCAGGAGAUGCCGAUGAUUCAGAUGCGGAUUUGGGUUCUGCCGUGAAACAGCUUCAGGAGUUCAUUCCUAACAUCAAGGACAGGGCCACCAGCACAAUCAAGCGGAUGUACCGGGACGACUUGGAACGGUUUAAGGAAUUUAAAGCACAAGGUGUCGCUAUUAAAUUUGGCAAGUUUUCUGUAAAGGAAAAUAAGCAGUUAGAGAAAAAUGUGGAAGACUUUCUAGCCCUGACAGGCAUUGAGAGUGCAGACAAGCUGCUGUACACGGACAGAUAUCCUGAGGAAAAAUCUGUGAUCACCAACUUAAAAAGGAGAUACUCGUUUAGAUUACACAUUGGUAGGAACAUUGCCCGGCCCUGGAAACUUAUAUACUAUCGAGCAAAGAAGAUGUUCGAUGUCAACAAUUACAAAGGCAGGUAUAGCGAAGGAGAUACUGAGAAGUUAAAGAUGUACCAUUCUCUCCUUGGGAAUGACUGGAAGACGAUUGGUGAGAUGGUGGCCCGAAGUAGCCUCUCCGUGGCCCUCAAGUUCUCACAGAUCAGCAGUCAAAGAAAUCGUGGUGCUUGGAGUAAGUCUGAAACCCGGAAACUAAUCAAGGCUGUCGAAGAAGUGAUUCUGAAGAAGAUGUCUCCCCAGGAGUUAAAAGAGGUGGAUUCCAAACUCCAAGAAAAUCCUGAAAGUUGCCUAUCAAUUGUUCGGGAAAAACUCUACAAGGGCAUAUCUUGGGUAGAAGUAGAAGCUAAAGUGCAAACCAGAAAUUGGAUGCAGUGUAAAAGUAAGUGGACAGAAAUUCUAACCAAGAGGAUGACUAAUGGUCGGCGUAUCUACUAUGGCAUGAAUGCCCUGCGGGCCAAGGUCAGCCUUAUUGAAAGGUUGUAUGAAAUAAAUGUGGAAGAUACUAAUGAAAUAGACUGGGAAGAUCUUGCUAGUGCCAUAGGUGAUGUUCCUCCAUCUUACGUUCAAACUAAAUUUUCUAGGCUGAAAGCUGUCUAUGUUCCAUUUUGGCAGAAAAAGACUUUUCCAGAGAUCAUCGACUACCUUUAUGAGACGACUCUACCUUUGCUGAAGGAAAAGUUAGAAAAAAUGAUGGAGAAAAAAGGCACUAAAAUCCAGACUCCUGCAGCACCCAAGCAAGUUUUCCCAUUUCGAGACAUCUUUUAUUAUGAAGACGAUAGUGAAGGAGAGGACAUAGAAAAAGAAAGCGAAGGCCAGGCGCCAUGCAUGGCUCACGCCUGUAAUUCCAGUACUUUGGGAGGCCAAGGCCGGUGGAUCAUCUGAGGUCAGGAGUUCGAGACCGGCCUGACCAACAUGGUGAAGACCUGUCACUAUUAAAAAUGCAAAAAUUAGCCGGGUGUGGUAGUGCACACCUGUAAUUUCAACUACUUGGGAGGCUGAGGCAGGAGAAUUGCUUGAACCCAGGAGGUGGAGGUUGCAGUGAGCCAAGAUCGCACCACCGCAUGAGAGAGAGAGAUUACUAUUUCUUGUCCCUUUUUCUCAGUUUGAUUAUAUUUAUAUACAUAUGUCAGUAAAUCUGUUUUCAGUAUUGAUGUUUAAUAAAGAAUGUACAAUGGCCAGAGUUCUACUCUUUCCUCUGGAGCAUUAAAAUAUAUUGCCAUUCCUAUUAAAACGUAUUUGAAUGUGAAAA